GUCUCAGCUCUCGGCUGGGGUUCGUCACUGGGCGCGGGAUUUGGCCGCCGCGGGGCUCCGGAGCCGCUCGCUCCCGACACGGCUCACGAUGCGCGGCGAGCAGGGCGCGGCGGGGGCCCGCGUGCUCCAGUUCACUAACUGCCGGAUCCUGCGCGGAGGGAAACUGCUCAGGGAGGAUCUGUGGGUGCGCGGAGGCCGCAUCUUGGACCCAGAGAAGCUGUUCUUUGAGGAGCGGCGCGUGGCCGACGAGCGGCGGGACUGCGGGGGCCGCAUCUUGGCUCCCGGAUUCAUCGACGUGCAGAUCAACGGUGGAUUUGGUGUUGACUUCUCUCAAGCCACGGAGGACGUGGGUUCGGGGGUUGCCCUCGUGGCCCGGAGGAUCCUGUCGCACGGCGUCACCUCCUUCUGCCCCACCCUGGUCACUUCCCCACCGGAGGUUUAUCACAAGGUUGUUCCUCAGAUCCCUGUGAAGAGUGGUGGUCCCCAUGGGGCAGGGGUCCUCGGGCUGCACCUGGAGGGCCCCUUCAUCAGCCGGGAGAAGCGGGGCGCGCACCCCGAGGCCCACCUCCGCUCCUUCGAGGCCGAUGCCUUCCAGGACUUGCUGGCCACCUACGGGCCCCUGGACAAUGUCCGCAUCGUGACGCUGGCCCCAGAGUUGGGCCGUAGCCACGAAGUGAUCCGGGCGCUGACGGCCCGUGGCAUCUGCGUGUCCCUAGGGCACUCAGUGGCUGACCUGCGGGCGGCAGAGGAUGCUGUGUGGAGCGGAGCCACCUUCAUCACCCACCUCUUCAACGCCAUGCUGCCUUUCCACCACCGCGACCCAGGCAUCGUGGGGCUCCUGACCAGCGACCGGCUGCCCGCAGGCCGCUGCAUCUUCUAUGGGAUGAUUGCAGAUGGCACGCACACCAACCCCGCCGCCCUGCGGAUCGCCCACCGUGCCCAUCCCCAGGGGCUGGUGCUGGUCACCGAUGCCAUCCCUGCCUUGGGCCUGGGCAACGGCCGGCACACGCUGGGACAGCAGGAAGUGGAAGUGGACGGUCUGACGGCCUACGUGGCAGGUGAGCGCCCUGACCCACUGGGUCCCAGGUCCCAGCCCGCAUGCCAGGUGGCCCACGACCCCCCCAGAGCCUGCCCUCUCUGCUCUCAAGGCACCAAGACGCUGAGUGGCAGCAUAGCCCCAAUGGACGUCUGUGUCCGGCACUUCCUGCAGGCCACAGGCUGCAGCAUGGAGUCGGCCCUGGAGGCUGCAUCCCUGCACCCCGCCCAGUUGCUGGGGCUGGAGAAGAGUAAGGGGACCCUGGACUUUGGUGCUGACGCAGACUUCGUGGUGCUCGACGACUCCCUUCACGUCCAGGCCACCUACAUCUCGGGUGAGCUGGUGUGGCAGGCGGACGCAGCUAGGCAGUGACAAGGACCUCGGCUGAGAGGACACCUGGCCGCAGCGGGAUGCCAUCAGGGCCGGGUGGUUGGGGAGCUGGUCUCCAGGGAGUGAGUCGGGAGCCCUGCUGGAUUGAUGCCCAGGGCCUGUGCGGCCGCCCUGGAGGCGGUGGCUGGGAUAAACGUGCACCCAGCAGGACUCGCCUUGGCUCCGGGUUUUGCUUGUGCUCACAUGUGGCACCAUCCUUGGUUGCCCUCCUGGAGAAGGCAUUCACGGCCUGGGGUGGGAUGGCUGGGCUGUAGUUUAGCCUGGGCCUUGGGCCCCAGUGGGGGACAGGGCCUGUCUGCAUGAAGUGGACCGGAGACCUGCAGACCCCAGGAAAGUGUCACUAUGGGAGGGAGGGGCAGGCAGUCAGUGGCUGGUGCCAUGGGGUGAAGCCACCAUGGGCUGGGGGUGAAGAGCCGGCAGGAAGGGGACCAGUCACAGGGAGUGUGGACAGUCAGGGGUUUGCUUUCUGCUCCUGAGUUGGGGUGUGCAGCGUGGAGCCCACAGCCUGGUUCUGGGCCAGGGCACAGUGCCAGGGGCUCCGCUCUGACCUCCAGGAGGGAGACUGGGCCCGGGACCCCUGUUUUCUGCUCCCUGGACUGCCUAGCCCUGAGUGCCACGGAUGACCAGCGUUCUGUUUUCUCUUCUCAAUAACCCUAUCUCUUCACACAUCCCCAGGCCCAGUGCUUGCCGGCUGUGGUGACCCUGCCUGGUGCUGGAGGGCAGUAUGGGAGGCACCAGUGUGCCCUGCUCACCCCAUUAGUGUCAUCCUGCCAUCUUCUGUGUCCCCUUGGCCCUGGCACACACCCAUGUGGCAAACACGGGCCGUGAGGCUCCCUGAACAGCUUCGAGGCGGGUGGGCUUCUGGAGCCCUCUUGGCUCUGAGGACAGCCACAGUGGGGUCAGACGUCAGGGAUUGGUGCAGCCCCACGUCAGGGGUGAUUGUCUUGACUUUCUCUCCAUUUGAGUUCUGGGGUGGGUGGCUCCCUUCCCCCUUGCUUACAGGUGCUGUCCUGGGCACAGGAGGUACGCGCCUGGCUCUGCCACUGUUCUCUUCCCUCUGCUGCAAAGCCCAGUUAAGGAAAUGUCUCCAGGUCCAAAGAGAUAGGAUGGUCUGGGCCCCACCUGUUGGAAGGGAACAGCCAGGGAAGAACCACCUGCCUGGGCAGGGCCUCGCCUGAGGGAGGGCCUGGGGCAGGGCACAAGGGGUUGAUCUCAGCCCACAAGCCCCAGGGGCAGCCCAGGAAAGCAGGCGACGGAUGUGGAUCCUGACCUCCUGAGAGGUGUGAGGUGCAGGGAUACCCACCUCUGCCUUGACGGCCGCGCACCCCUUAGGAAGUGGCUGUCCAGCGCCUGCCUGUGCUGGGCCUGGGAGAGGAGCUGUCUUGCCAGGGCUCCCAGGCAGGGAGAGGCAGGUGAGGUUCUCAGCCGAUGUGUUAGAGGUUGAGCAUCGCCUGUGCCCAGCUUGCUGGCUGUCAGUGCUUGAUGUGCCCAUCCUCAGCUAAAACCCAGAGCUGGCAUGUUGGUCAUCCCCACCUCAGACGGGACGCCCAGUCCAGAGCUGGUGAGCCCUGGGCCAGCCUUUGGGCCUGGCCUGCCCCAUUCACCGGCCAGCGCCCCACCUCCCUGGCUGGAGGGUCGGGGAGGGGCUGGCAGAGAUGGUUGGUCCACAGGGCUAGCCCUGGGUGGUGGGAGAGGGGCCCAGGGUCAGGGUGAGAGAGAGCUGGGCCAGGGAGCUGCUGCAGGAUGAUUUUGAGGUGUGGGGGAAGCACUCUUGGUUGGUUUUGGUUUGCUUUUUAAAAAUUGUGGUAAAAUACAUAACAAAAGUAACUAUCGUAA